GCGGAGCCCAGGCCCUAGGGAAUCGUGGGGUCGUAUCCCGCGGGUGGAGGCCGGGGUGGCGCCGGCCGGGGCGGGGGAGCCCAAAAGACCGGCUGCCGCCUGCUCCCCGGAAAAGGGCACUCGUCUCCGUGGGUGUGGCGGAGCGCGCGGUGCAUGGAAUGGGCUAUGUGAAUGAAAAAAGGUAUCCGUUAUGAAACUUCCAGAAAAACGAGCUACAUUUUUCAGCCGCAGCACGGUCCUUGGCAAACAAGGAUGAGAAAAAUAUCCAACCACGGGAGCCUGCGGGUGGCGAAGGUGGCAUACCCCCUGGGGCUGUGUGUGGGCGUGUUCAUCUAUGUUGCCUACAUCAAGUGGCACCGGGCCACCGCCACCCAGGCCUUCUUCAGCAUCACCAGGGCAGCCCCGGGGGCCCGGUGGGGUCAGCAGGCCCACAGCCCCCUGGGGACAGCUGCAGACGGGCACGAGGUCUUCUACGGGAUCAUGUUUGAUGCAGGAAGCACUGGCACCCGAGUACACGUCUUCCAGUUCACCCGGCCCCCCAGAGAAACUCCCACGUUAACCCACGAAACCUUCAAAGCACUGAAGCCAGGUCUUUCUGCCUAUGCUGAUGAUGUUGAAAAGGCUGUCUUCACAAAGGAAGGGGGCUUUGACAGUGCUGCCUGGGCAUUUCAUGCCAUUUGGGAUGGUCAGAAGAGAGAAGGUGUGCAGCGCGCGAGCCCAGAGGAGAACGCGCCCCCACCCGGCCCCAUCCUCUGACUCCACCGUGCCAGCGCUCACUUCUCCAACGUGGGGGUCCCGAGGUCUUGGUACAGAGCGCUCAGGGAAUCCGGGAACUACUGGAUGUUGCUAAACAGGACAUUCCGUUCGACUUCUGGAAGGCCACCCCUCUGGUCCUCAAGGCCACAGCUGGCUUACGCCUGUUACCUGGAGAAAAGGCCCAGAAGUUACUGCAGAAGGUGAAAAAAGUAUUUAAAGCAUCGCCUUUCCUUGUAGGGGAUGACUGUGUUUCCAUCAUGAACGGAACAGAUGAAGGCGUUUCGGCGUGGAUCACCAUCAACUUCCUGACAGGCAGCUUGAAAACUCCAGGAGGGAGCAGCGUGGGCAUGCUGGACUUGGGCGGAGGAUCCACUCAGAUCGCCUUCCUGCCACGCGUGGAGGGCACCCUGCAGGCCUCCCCACCCGGCUACCUGACGGCACUGCGGAUGUUUAACAGGACCUACAAGCUCUAUUCCUACAGCUACCUCGGGCUCGGGCUGAUGUCGGCACGCCUGGCGAUCCUGGGCGGCGUGGAGGGGCAGCCUGCUAAGGAUGGAAAGGAGUUGGUCAGCCCUUGCUUGUCUCCCAGUUUCAAAGGAGAGUGGGAACACGCAGAAGUCACGUACAGGGUUUCAGGGCAGAAAGCAGCGGCAAGCCUGCACGAGCUGUGUGCUGCCAGAGUGUCAGAGGUCCUUCAAAACAGAGUGCACAGGACGGAGGAAGUGAAGCAUGUGGACUUCUAUGCUUUCUCCUACUAUUACGACCUUGCAGCUGGUGUGGGCCUCAUAGAUGCGGAGAAGGGAGGCAGCCUGGUGGUGGGGGACUUCGAGAUCGCAGCCAAGUACGUGUGUCGGACCCUGGAGACACAGCCGCAGAGCAGCCCCUUCUCAUGCAUGGACCUCACCUACGUCAGCCUGCUACUCCAGGAGUUCGGCUUUCCCAGGAGCAAAGUGCUGAAGCUCACUCGGAAAAUUGACAAUGUUGAGACCAGCUGGGCUCUGGGGGCCAUUUUUCAUUACAUCGACUCCCUGAACAGACAGAAGAGUCCAGCCUCAUAGUGGCCGAGCCAUCCCUGUCCCCGUCAGCAGUGUCUGUGUGUCUGCAUAAACCCUCCUGUCCUGGACGUGACUUCAUCCUGAGGAGCCACAGCACAGGCCGUGCUGGCACUUUCUGCACACUGGCUCUGGGACUUGCAGAAGGCCUGGUGCUGCCCUGGCAUCAGCCUCUUCCAGUCACAUCUGGCCAGAGGGCUGUCUGGACCUGGGCCCUGCUCAAUGCCACCUGUCUGCCUGGGCUCCAAGUGGGCAGGACCAGGACAGAACCACAGGCACACACUGAGGGGGCAGUGUGGCUCCCUGCCUGUCCCAUCCCCAUGCCCCGUCCGCGGGGCUGUGGCUGCUGCUGUGCAUGUCCCUGCGAUGGGAGUCUUGUCUCCCAGCCUGUCAGUUUCCUCCCCAGGGCAGAGCUCCCCUUCCUGCAAGAGUCUGGGAGGCGGUGCAGGCUGUCCUGGCUGCUCUGGGGAAGCCGAGGGACAGCCAUAACACCCCCGGGACAGUAGGUCUGGGCGGCACCACUGGGAACUCUGGACUUGAGUGUGUUUGCCUCUUCCUUGGGUAUGAAUGUGUGAGUUCACCCAGAGGCCUGCUCUCCUCACACAUUGUGUGGUUUGGGGUUAAUGAUGGAGGGAGACACCUCCUCAUAGACGGCAGGUGCCCACCUUUCAGGGAGUCUCCCAGCAUGGGCGGAUGCCGGGCAUGAGCUGCUGUAAACUAUUUGUGGCUGUGCUGCUUGAGUGACGUCUCUGUCGUGUGGGUGCCAAGUGCUUGUGUAGAAACUGUGUUCUGAGCCCCCUUUUCUGGACACCAACUGUGUCCUGUGAAUGUAUCGCUACUGUGAGCUGUUCCCGCCUAGCCAGGGCCAUGUCUUAGGUGCAGCUGUGCCACGGGUCAGCUGAGCCACAGUCCCAGAACCAAGCUCUCGGUGUCUCGGGCCACCAUCCGCCCACCUCGGGCUGACCCCACCUCCUCCAUGGACAGUGUGAGCCCCGGGCCGUGCAUCCUGCUCAGUGUGGCGUCAGUGUCGGGGCUGAGCCCCUUGAGCUGCUUCAGUGAAUGUACAGUGCCCGGCACGAGCUGAACCUCAUGUGUUCCACUCCCAAUAAAAGGUUGACAGGGGCUUCUCCUUCUCUGGGAUUCCUCUCGUUGAGCGACAGUAGCAUUUGCCCACCUGGCACCUGAGAUCCCUGUUUACUAAACCUUAGAAAAGCUGCCAAAGGGGGUGGCGUAUUUCCAGUCCUGUCGACAUCCCUCUCGAGGACACAGCAGUGGAGGGCCCCUGGGGGCUGGGGCUGGUGAAGGGUCUGGCUGGUGGCCCCGGCCCUCCCAGCGUCUGUUGAGCACAGCUCCUCCUGUGCCAGGCCAGCAGCCCACAGCACGGCCAGGUGAGGCCUGGGCACAUAACCUCGAGUGAGCUGCAAGUCCCCAUGUCAUUCUGUUCAGCAAGGAUCUGGUUUUGGUCUGGAAGCGUCCCAAAGGUGUCGCAUGCCAGGGAAACUGCAGACCAGCCCACAUCCCGAGUGCUUGUGCCUGAAGCCCCCCCCAACCAACUGUCACAGGAGGACAGGAUCUGGCCCUAGGGCCUCCCAGGGCUGCAGCGAAUGCUGAUGGAGCCACGUGGUGGAGGCCUGCACAGAGCAGGAAAGGACAAAAGACAAAAAGAGGAACAGUUUCCUCCCUCCCGCCUGGGCUGGGUCCCCACCAGCGCCUUUACUUCCAUAAUAUCCACCAGCUUAAAUAUUUAAAGAACUCCGGAGGCUGAGAAUCAGACGCAUGAAGGUAAAGCCAAAAUCAAUUUGGUCCAUUUAAAGAAGGUCGGUGACCUCAUGCCUGAAAAAGGCAAACAACUGGAAGUUUUCCAAAAGUGCACCAAAUAAGUCAUGGAAUAUUUCUGGGCCCGGCAAAGUAUGCAAGUCAUUUCUCUCUGAGUGUCUUUUGUGAUAAUGAAGUAGGCUCUCAUUUGUCAAAAAUAGCUACACGUGCACAUCGUAAAAGAAGCAAACUAGGGUUGCUUGAAAAUUCUGUUCCCUCAGGAUGUGUGCAUUGACAAGCUCAGACAGGUCUCACACGCCCCACAUGCCACCCCAGCCCGCGUACCCCACAUCACUUAGCACCCAUUGCUGCCCACUGAGCUGCCUCAGUCCUGCAGUCCCCGUGUUUGGAUGGCAGGAUCCCAGGGCAGUGAGUUUCAGGGCAUAAGCAGACGUUGCCACGUUGCCUUCAAUCCUACUGGACAAGCAUCGGUGCUGGCCUCCCCCAUGUCCUAACAGCUACAGCCAGUUUAAUCUUUGCCAUUCUGGCAGAUUUAAAAAAAUGAUAACUGGUAGUUUUAAUAUGCAUGGAUCUAAUUCAUCGGGUAUAUCUAAGUUGUAUUUCCGUGAAACAUCUGUUCAUAUCCCUUGCCGAUUUUCUAUAAGAUUGUCAUCAUUUUUUUGUUAAUUGUAGAUCUUUAUUUAUUAAGGAAAUUAUCCCAUUAUGAUA